GCGUAGUCGGGGACGCCGGGCCGAGGCUUUGCUAGGGAACACUGUUAUCGCCCCGCCCCCUCGGAGCUUUUUCUCCAGUUAACUGUCGGAGUAGCGGGGGCUCCGGCGCCGGGCGACAUGCCGGUGCGCUUCAAGGGGCUGAGUGAAUACCAGAGGAACUUCCUGUGGAAAAAGUCUUAUUUGUCCGAGUCUUGUAAUUCCUCCGUGGGGCGAAAGUACCCAUGGGCUGGACUUAGAUCAGAUCAAUUAGGAAAUCAAGGCAGAUGUAGAACCAAGAUCCAGCACAGUGACAUCUCAUCCCUUCUCAUCUUGGUCUGCUCCACAUAAGAGAAGCUUUGUGAAAAGUUCCAAAUUUUGACAGUACCAGGGCCCAUUGUUCUGUUAAGUAGCACAGGAAAGUAAUUAGAAACGAGGCAGCAUGUACUGCCUGGCCUGCCAGGUCUAUCACGUUGCAAUUCUAGUGACUUUUGUUAGGAUAACUGGAACAUUUUGUGACCCCCUGAUUUUUAAUUUUUUGUUAUGGUCAAAUUUUUAAUGCUUUUAAAAGCAAAAUUAAAUAUUUUAUGUUGAAAAGCUGUACUUUUAAAAUCCUAUAAUCUGAAGGAUAUUGUGUGUAUAUAUAGGUACAUAUAUCUGAACUAAAUUUAAAAUUUCAUUUCUCCUCCACAAGUGUUCUUAAAAGUUGUCUUUGUAACUUUUUGCUUUAGUAGCUACUAUUUUUGUAUACCGUGUUUUGUAGGCAUCACGAAAGAGCCAAGUUUUAUUUCAAAAAGAAGAGUCCCUUACCAUGACCCACAGAUUUCAAAAUCUCUGGAGUGGAAUGGAGCUAUCUCAGAGAGCAAUGUGGUUGCAUCACCAGAACCAGAAGCCCCGGAAACACCAAAAUCACAAGAAGCAGAACAAAAGGAUGUUACUCAAGAAAGAGUUCACUCACUAGAAGCUUCCAGGGUUCCCAAAAGAACCAGAUCUCACUCUGCAGACUCCAGAGCUGAAGGGGCUUCAGAUGUGGAAAAUAAUGAGGGUGUAACAAACCAUACACCAGUUAAUGAAAAUGUGGAACUGGAACAUUCUACCAAGGUUCUUUCAGAAAAUGUAGAUAAUGGGGUAGGCAUAUUCACUGCAUUUCUUUUCAAAAGCAUAGAAUUCUUCAUUGGUUUCAUUGUCAUUUCUGUAAUAUUACAUUUUGUGUUUCAGAAUUUUCCAUUGUUGUUUUCUUGUCUAAUGUCUAUAAGAAUAGUUGAUAACAGGCUGUUGACUUUAGUUAUUGUGAAUUAGUUCUAUUCUGACUACUCGCUAUUUUGUAGUAGUUGUACUAUGAUAAUCUGUUUAUUGGAUGGACCUCCUGCGUCUGGAUUUUAUUCAUCAUAUAUUAGCACCUGAGUCCUAAGGGAGAGAUCAAGUUGAGACAGAGAAGGGAAGUAGGCCCUUACUUCUGGCAGGGUGCUGAGCUGACUUCUACCUAGCCCCUUUUCAGUUUCUUAUCGUGUACAAGAAGACAAACAGAAAUUCAAUUGAUGAAAUGCAAAAGGAAGGAGAGCUCUGGCUGUCUCUCAGAGAUCUUGCAUUUCUGCUCUCUUAUGUCACAGCUGGCCUGCAGCAGGUCCCUGUGAGCACAUAAGCAGAGGCUGCAGGAACUUGUGUGGGGAUCUCAAUGCUUUCCACAUUUCUUUCUCCAUUCUGUUCCACUGCUCUUCUCUGGUUCAUGUCCACCACUGACUGGGACCCUGAAGAGGCAUUUCAGAGUGUUGGAGAAGAAUCUGUAGCUUGUUGAAAAAGCUGGGGGUGAAAGGGAACAAGGAAGGUGAUGUGUGAGUCUGGCAGGCAGGAGAAGGGGUGUUCAUAGAAGCAGUGUGCAGGUGAGGCAAAGUGCUGGGACUUUUUGGUAAUAGAUUUAAUUAUGAAUGAUUAGUAGGAAAGGACUGAGAGUAUUAUAUUUUUCCUGGGAUGCCUAAUAGUCCUUUGAUAGAAAGGAAUUUUAAAUAGUUUGACACUUGAAAAAAGAUACUAUUUAUAAGUUGAAGAAAGUUUGCUGUACCACAAUGCGCAUGUAGUUAACAAUUUUGCACUGUAGAUUUAACAUUUUGUUAAGAGGAUAGAUUUCAUGUUAUGCAUUUUUUACCACAAUUUUUAAAAAGUUUGAAUAGAAAUUUUUAAUGUCUUUGAGUGGAUUUUGUUUUUUGAACAGUUGGAUAGACUUCUGCGUAAGAAAGCUGGAUUGACUGUUGUUCCUUCAUAUAAUGCCUUGAGAAAUUCUGAAUAUCAAAGGCAGUUUGUUUGGAAGACUUCUAAAGAAACUGCUCCAGCUUUUGCAGCCAAUCAGGUAGCUUAAUGGAUGUAAUACAUUUCUGAGUACCAUUAUCUUAUCUAGUAAUGUAGAUUUACAUAGAAUUAAGAGUUGAAAGAAAUUAAGUACUUAAGUAGCCUGGAGGUAGGUUCUAGAAAACCAAAAUGAGAGUUUUGCUAAAAUCAUCCUAUUACUUAUGAUUUAUGGUAGUAAUAUUAUACUGUCCUAGGCUUCUGAUGAUCAUUGUUGCCAGAUGCAGCACAUAUACUAAAUAUGAGACAGGGUAAUGAAAACUUGGGGAACUGGUAAGUUUUUGCAUGCUACAAGAUUUUUUUACUUAUUAAAAAAUUAUUAAAUUGAUUUUAUUCUAAAAUGUUGUGUUUUGUUGACUAAUAUAUUGCGUGUUUCCUGUAUUCUAAGAAAGGCGUAACUGCUUUGAAUAUUUAAUAAAUACAAAAUAUGUUGACAGUAACACAAGAUACGUAAUUUUGUCCUUGUAUCAGACAAAUAGUAAUAGGCAUUGUCAGUAUAACUAUAUUUGUAAAAUUCAAAAGCUGUAAUGAUGUGGUAUUAGAUUUCAUUAUACUCCUGCACAAUUUUAGUAUUGAGAUACCAUUACUAAUAGAUAGUCUGUUGUUUUACUACCUUCAUCCUUUAGGGAGUUCUUAGGCUUUAAACUCUCAUUUAUGUUCUUAACAGUACUUCUAGGCAUAGACAGGAAAUACCUCCACUUGGAAUAUCCCCAGAGACCUGUAAUGGCUUAGUCUGUUUUUUCUUCUGGUCUUCGUGUUUUUCUUUAUAAAUACACACACUUUCACACACCCUCACAUUCAUUUUCUCCUGUACGUCAACAUUCACUUGUAUAUUUUGUAUAGCCGUAAGAACUGACAGGAUAAUUAGAUUCAGCAAGACAAUAACAUCUAGUCAUCUUACAUUAAGAUAGAAAAACACCAGUGAUCCUAUAAAUUGUGGCAGCUUUGGGCUUAAUUAUUAUUCAAUUUUUAAAAUACCUUUGAAAUUUAUAUAACAUUUUAAGAAUCUGUGAAGUAACAAAGUGAUAAAUACCCUUUAUUAACCUAGUAAAUAGGAUCAGUACUUCUUUUGCUUGCCUACAGGUUUUUUUGGAGAUUAAGUGUACCUAAAACAUUACUUACAACCUGAAAAUUGUAAUUAUUCAGUUUUUUAUAGAGUAUUUGACCUUUAAAAUAGAGCUGAUUCAAAUCAAAGCCCUAUCAUCAUCAAAUAGGGCUUUUACAUGUCAGUGAAAGCGUUGUGUAGAAACGUUACUUUUAUAAGAGAAAUCACUAGCGAUAUAUUCAGUAGUUUUACUGCUUUCUUUAAUAAGUGUUUCACAUACUUUUUUUAGAAGGAAAUGCUCAUGGUUAGUUCAAAGCAUAUUGAAUUCAGAGUCUAUGGAUUGAAGAGCUUUGAGACAGCUUUCAAUGCUUGUUGAUAGGAAACCUCUAAAAGGGUUGUUCAUUUCAUUUUAUCAGACACCUGCUUUCUGAAAGGAUGUCUUAUAUUAAUAUGUAAAGGAGUCAGAACAGUUUUUGGCAGUAAAGUCCUUGAGGUUAUACUGUACUAAAAAAGAUAAACUGUUUAGAUCUGAUCUGUAUGAAGAUGUACUAUCCAGCAUUACAAAGCAGUAAUAUAACUUGACUGAGUUCCCCAUCUUUUCCAUUUGCUUUCCUUGUAAUCAGUGGUAAUAUGCCGUGAAAUAGAAACCAUAUUGUGAAGUAGUAAGUAUAAAAGGAAAUAUUUAACAAUAGAAGUGUAGUAAUUGCUCAGAACAUUUUCUUUGCCUUAAUAAAAUACGCUGAAAAUAAGCCAAGGGAAGAAAAGCUAAACAAAUUGAACAUAUUGGGUAUUCAGAAAUGUGAAGAAUUUUCUAUUAAGGCAGGAAGAAAAAAAAUCAUGUCAGGGAGGAAGAAAAAAACCUGUAGAACUGACAACAGAGUUGCCUUAAAGCUAAUGUCUAUGUCAUAUGAAAAUAUGCCAACGUUUAUUUUGAUUAUAAGCUAUAUUUUGAUUACAAAACUGUUAUUCAAAACAUAGUAAUGAGUACAUAAAGUUGACCUUUGGAUGUUAAUAAUAUAUGUGAAAUGAAAUUAAAAUCAUAUAUAACUUUGCUA